CUCGGCAGCCGCCUGUCGCCGCGGGAGCAGCCGCUAUCUCUGUGUGUCCGCGUGUGCGCCCGGUCCCCGCCUGCCGCACCAUGGAGAGCUACCACAAGCCUGACCAGCAGAAGCUGCAGGCCUUGAAGGACACGGCCAACCGCCUACGUAUCAGCUCCAUCCAGGCCACCACUGCGGCGGGCUCUGGCCACCCCACGUCAUGCUGCAGCGCCGCAGAGAUCAUGGCUGUCCUCUUUUUCCACACCAUGCGCUACAAGUCCCAGGACCCCCGGAAUCCGCACAAUGACCGCUUUGUGCUCUCCAAGGGCCAUGCAGCUCCCAUCCUCUACGCGGUCUGGGCUGAAGCUGGUUUCCUGGCCGAGGCGGAGCUGCUGAACCUGAGGAAGAUCAGCUCCGACUUGGACGGGCACCCGGUCCCGAAACAAGCUUUCACCGACGUGGCCACUGGCUCCCUGGGCCAGGGCCUCGGGGCCGCUUGUGGGAUGGCCUACACCGGCAAAUACUUCGACAAGGCCAGCCUCCCGAGUAGCUGGGACUACAGCUACCGAGUCUAUUGCUUGCUGGGAGACGGGGAGCUGUCAGAGGGCUCUGUAUGGGAGGCCAUGGCCUUCGCCAGCAUCUAUAAGCUGGACAACCUUGUGGCCAUUCUAGACAUCAAUCGCCUGGGCCAGAGUGACCCGGCCCCACUGCAGCACCAGAUGGACAUCUACCAGAAGCGGUGCGAGGCCUUCGGUUGGCAUGCCAUCAUCGUGGAUGGACACAGCGUGGAGGAGCUGUGCAAGGCCUUUGGCCAGGCCAAGCACCAGCCAACAGCCAUCAUUGCCAAGACCUUCAAGGGCCGAGGGAUCACGGGGGUAGAAGAUAAGGAGUCUUGGCAUGGGAAGCCCCUCCCCAAAAACAUGGCUGAGCAGAUCAUCCAGGAGAUCUACAGCCAGAUCCAGAGCAAAAAGAAGAUCCUGGCAACCCCUCCACAGGAGGACGCACCCUCAGUGGACAUUGCCAACAUCCGCAUGCCCAGCCUGCCCAGCUACAAAGUUGGGGACAAGAUAGCCACCCGCAAGGCCUACGGGCAGGCACUGGCCAAGCUGGGCCAUGCCAGUGACCGCAUCAUCGCCCUGGAUGGGGACACCAAAAAUUCCACCUUCUCGGAGAUCUUCAAAAAGGAGCACCCGGACCGCUUCAUCGAGUGCUACAUUGCUGAGCAGAACAUGGUGAGCAUCGCGGUGGGCUGUGCCACCCGCAACAGGACGGUGCCCUUCUGCAGCACUUUUGCAGCCUUCUUCACGCGGGCCUUUGACCAGAUUCGCAUGGCCGCCAUCUCCGAGAGCAACAUCAACCUCUGCGGCUCCCACUGCGGCGUUUCCAUCGGGGAAGACGGGCCCUCCCAGAUGGCCCUAGAAGAUCUGGCUAUGUUUCGGUCAGUCCCCACAUCAACUGUCUUUUACCCAAGUGAUGGCGUUGCUACAGAGAAGGCAGUGGAACUAGCCGCCAAUACAAAGGGUAUCUGCUUCAUCCGGACCAGCCGCCCAGAAAAUGCCAUCAUCUAUAACAACAAUGAGGACUUCCAGGUCGGACAAGCCAAGGUGGUCCUGAAGAGCAAGGAUGACCAGGUGACCGUUAUCGGGGCUGGGGUGACCCUGCACGAGGCCUUGGCCGCUGCCGAACUGCUGAAGAAAGAAAAGAUCAACAUCCGCGUGCUGGACCCCUUCACCAUCAAGCCCCUGGACAGAAAACUCAUUCUCGACAGCGCUCGUGCCACCAAGGGCAGGAUCCUCACCGUGGAGGACCAUUAUUAUGAAGGUGGCAUUGGUGAGGCUGUGUCCAGUGCAGUAGUGGGCGAGCCUGGCAUCACUGUCACCCACCUGGCAGUUAACCGGGUACCAAGAAGUGGGAAGCCGGCUGAGCUGCUGAAGAUGUUUGGUAUCGACAGGGAUGCCAUUGCACAAGCUGUGAGGGGCCUCAUCACCAAGGCCUAGGGCGGGUAUGAAGUGUGGGGCGGGGGUCUAUACAUUCCUGAGAUUCUGGGAAAGGUGCUCAAAGAUGUACUGAGAGGAGGGGUAAAUAUAUGUUUUGAGAAAAAUGAAUUGGCCCUGAAAUGUUUUCUUUUUUGAUGUGUUUGCAGCCAGUGCAGGUUCUGGGGAAGAAGCGUGGAGGGUGCGCUAGGGAGGCUGGUGUCCUUGGUCCUGGGCCAGGACCUGGGUGUCCCAAGUCCCCUUGGAAUCACCUGCAACUGCCCUCAACCUCCAGAACUAUCGCUGCCUCCCAUUCAUCACCAGGUGACAUUUGACUGCAACCUGCCUUCUAGCUGAGAGGCUGAGACCUACAUCCCUCAUUGUGACCUCAGUCCACCUGGCCCUGAGCGGGCUGGGGAACUGCCUCAGUCUGGAAGCUGACCAGGCACUCUCAGGGCCGCCCCACCUCCCCCAAGUCCCCACAGCCUUGCAGUCAGGUCUCCUGGGAUAGGGAGGUUCACUUGCUUGUUGUCCCUCGUCCUUGUCAUAUCCUUUUAACUAGGCAUCUCAGAGAAGCAGAGACAGGGCAGCCUUCGUCCUGGGGGAAAAGGGACCCUCAGGAUGGCAUGAGAGGUCCUCAAUCCCAAGUGUGGAACUGUCCCCCUCAACUUGUUAAAAUGCAGAUUUCUGGGUCUUGCCAAUGGGGCCUGGGACUCCAUGUGACAACUGGCCCAGGAGCUUCUGAUGUCACACAGAAUUCUGCAGUCCCAAGCUCCAGCCCCGACCUGCUCUGCUGUUCCUAGGUGACUGCCCUCACACUGCUGACCACAGUGGAUUUCUCCCCCUGCUGCUCGGGCUCAGCUGGGGUCAGCCCUGCUUAUAAGGUCAACUGUGCAAAACCUUAUACUGGCCAAGAACAAACUAGUGCUGGGGGAGGAGGGCUGGGUGCCCCGGCCACUGGUGGAGUCCCCAGGAAAUCCUCAGAGCUGUUGCGAGGAUGAGACACAUUUGUGGACACGUCCACCUGUCCUCCUGACCGUCUGGAGAGAAUAAACCUGUCAAAGCCAA